GGUGACGUCCUCCCAAGAUGGCGGAGACAGAGUGAAGAAACUGUGUUCCCCCCUUGGGUUGCUAUCGGUGGUAGAAGUGUUGCCAUUCACCGUCACUUAUUGAUGUGUCCAAAGGAUUGUGUUAGUUGAUCAAGAUCAAGGGUAAAAUUCCAUUCUGAUAUCAAAAUGCAGUAUUCGCACCACUGUGAGCACCUUUUAGAGAGACUGAACAAACAGCGGGAAGCAGGUUUUCUCUGUGACUGUACCAUAGUGAUUGGGGAAUUCCAGUUUAAAGCUCAUAGGAAUGUGCUGGCCUCCUUUAGUGAGUAUUUUGGUGCGAUCUACAGAAGCACUUCUGAGAACAAUGUCUUUCUUGAUCAGAGUCAGGUGAAGGCUGAUGGAUUUCAGAAACUGUUGGAGUUUAUAUACACAGGAACUUUAAAUCUUGACAGUUGGAAUGUUAAAGAAAUUCAUCAGGCUGCUGACUAUCUCAAAGUGGAAGAGGUGGUCACUAAAUGCAAAAUAAAGAUGGAAGAUUUUGCUUUUAUUGCUAAUCCUUCUUCUACAGAGAUAUCUAGUAUUACUGGAAACAUUGAAUUGAAUCAACAGACUUGUCUUCUUACUCUGCGAGAUUAUAAUAAUCGAGAGAAAUCAGAAGUAUCUACAGAUUUGAUUCAGGCAAAUCCUAAACAAGGCGCGUUAGCGAAAAAGUCAUCUCAAACGAAAAAGAAGAAGAAGGCUUUCAACUCCCCGAAAACAGGGCAGAAUAAAACAGUGCAAUAUCCCAGUGACAUCUUAGAGAAUGCAUCUGUUGAAUUAUUCCUAGAUGCAAAUAAACUGCCCACACCUGUAGUAGAACAAGUUGCACAAAUAAAUGAUAAUUCAGAACUCGAGUUGACAUCAGUUGUGGAAAAUACUUUUCCAGCACAAGAUAUUGUGCACACUGUUACAGUGAAACGGAAACGUGGAAAAUCACAGCCAAACUGUGCUCUGAAAGAACACUCUAUGUCUAAUAUAGCCAGCGUCAAGAGUCCUUAUGAGGCGGAGAACUCCGGGGAAGAGCUGGAUCAGAGGUAUUCCAAGGCCAAGCCAAUGUGUAACACAUGUGGGAAAGUGUUUUCAGAAGCCAGCAGUUUGAGAAGGCACAUGAGAAUACAUAAAGGAGUCAAACCUUACGUCUGCCACUUAUGUGGAAAGGCAUUUACCCAAUGUAACCAGCUGAAAACGCAUGUAAGAACUCAUACAGGUGAGAAGCCAUACAAAUGUGAAUUGUGUGAUAAAGGAUUUGCUCAGAAAUGUCAGCUAGUCUUCCAUAGUCGCAUGCAUCAUGGUGAAGAAAAACCCUAUAAAUGUGAUGUAUGCAACUUACAGUUUGCAACUUCUAGCAAUCUCAAGAUUCAUGCAAGGAAGCAUAGUGGAGAGAAGCCAUAUGUCUGUGAUAGGUGUGGACAGAGAUUUGCUCAAGCCAGCACACUGACCUAUCAUGUCCGUAGGCAUACUGGAGAAAAGCCUUAUGUAUGUGAUACCUGUGGGAAGGCAUUUGCUGUCUCUAGUUCUCUUAUCACUCAUUCUCGAAAACAUACAGGUGAAAAACCAUACAUAUGUGGUAUUUGUGGGAAAAGUUUUAUUUCCUCAGGAGAGCUCAACAAACACUUUCGGUCCCAUACAGGAGAAAGACCAUUUAUCUGCGAAUUAUGUGGAAAUUCUUACACAGAUAUUAAAAAUUUAAAGAAGCACAAAACAAAAGUCCAUUCUGGUGCAGAUAAAACUCUAGACUCCAGUGCAGAGGAUCAUACUUUGAGUGAACAGGAUUCCAUACAAAAAAGUCCUUUAUCAGAAACUAUGGAUGUGAAGCCUUCUGAUAUGACUUUACCAUUAGCUCUUCCACUUGGGACUGAGGACCAUCACAUGCUUCUGCCUGUCACGGAUACUCAGUCUCCUACAUCAGAUACAUUGUUGAGGUCAACUGUGAAUGGGUAUUCAGAACCACAGUUGAUUUUUUUACAACAAUUAUACUGACUUUGUAAGGAAUAUGGAAUUGCUAAGAUAUCAUUGGUAGCAAACAUCUCUGGUAAGGUGCAUAUAUUCAUAUUAAAUUCCCAUUCAUUUGAGUUGUGACCAUUAUUUUUCAUUCACUGAAGUAAAAGCACCUGAUGCUGCAUCACAACUGCAAUGUUUGUUUUUAUUUUUGGCUUUAUGUCUAUACUCCACAGAGAGCUUUUUAAGUAAUGAAUUAUGUAGCACUAUUUUGGGUGGAUGAGUUUUAUUUUCUUUUAAAGCUGCCUUAAUUCCAUUUUUAUUUUGCAUUUUAGAAUUGCCCUUCAUUUACUAAAUCAGCCAGUUAAUGUGAUUCAGUUGUGACCUGUGGGAUUUUAAAAUUUUCCUGCCCUCAUAAUUUAAGCAAAAUCCACGAUAGUAUCAGCCCAAGAGUGUGUUGCUAUUUGUAAGCCCCAUGGAUCAAUACAUAAACUAUGCAUAAAAAUAAAAUUUCAUAUUUUCGCUCGUAAAAAUUUAGGCGCUGAAUAAGAAUUGUGCUAUUUCUCUAUUAAUAUAUUGUUAGAAAUAACUUUUCUAAUGAAACAAAAAUGUUUCUCAAAAUCUAGAAAAGUGCAUAUAAAUUUUUGUUCAUUUAGAACUGAGUAUUCUGGAGAAAACCAAUGGUCAGCACUUUUGGUUUGAGUUAUCUGAGAUUGUAUUUUCAAAAUGAAUUUUAAGUAGAUAUUUGGUGUUUUUAUCUUGUCAAAGACAGUUUCAAAAUUUGAUUCAGUUUAUGUUUUAUUCCGUUCUAAAAUAUUGGAGAUGAGGAAAAUGUACUUGAGUUUUGAAAUAUUUUGGUAAGCCUCUCUUACUCCUGUUAUGCACUUUUUAAAAUAAAUACUGAAUUCCAGAAAGAAUUUUCUAGAUAUAAACUUAAUGCAUACUAGAAAUCACUUGGCUUCUAAAUUUGGUACAUUAUAUUGCAUAAAGAGUUAAGAAAUUAACCUCAAUUAUAAGUAAACAUUUUGAGUUACCAGAAAGCCAACUAUAGUUAAAUAUUUUAUAUCUGAGUUUUCUAUAAGUUUGGGGUUUGUUAAUUUUAUAAAUUAAACCACAACUUUUGGUGGUGGUUGUAGUUUCACAAUGGUCCUUUUCCUUCCAAAUGAAUGUAGAAAAUUCGUUAUUAUCCUGAUAUUUGCACCACUCAUCCCCAUGCCACUUUUCCCACAUAUUAAUUUAUUUCACUGCCUGAUCUUUGGAUAUGAAAUUAUGAGUUCCACAAAGUCAAUUUUUAUAGUGCCAAUCAAACAGCAUGGUGAUAUUCUUUUUCUUUUUUUUUCCCCCCACAAGGCUGUUGUUCAGUGUGAGAUGACAUCAUUUCUUAUUUCUGCCAUGCUGUGGCUUUUUUGUGUUCUGCUUUUAAACUACACCUGUAGUACAGUUAAUAUGUUUUUUAUUGGUAUUGAUUUCUUUAAUUCAUUAAUUUUCUCUAUUUGGGACCCAAGUCAUAAGAACCAAUUAGAGGACAUAAUAAAAACACUUAAUGCUUGUAGUCUGUAGAGAUCUUCACCAUUUCACAGCACACACAUUAUUUUCAUAAUAAAUUGCCACUGGUGGGACAUGGGACUGACUUAUUUGAAUAGAGUUUGAAAUACCACCUUUGUAUGAUGCAAACAAUAUUUGAUUAUUUUAUCUAAGAAAUCUAUGCAUGUGUAUCAAGUUAAAAUAGUGGGUUUAAAUACAAUUUACAAAGCAUUAGAAUGUUACCUAAUCUCUUCUGGGUUAAAUGUGAUAGGAAUGUAUUGGAAUGUGAAGAAAUUAUAGAAAAUUAAAAGACUCAGCCUCUUUAGGAAGUUUGCUAAAAUGGAGAGGUUAUGUUUAAUUUAUUUAUAUCUUCGUUAAUCCAAGCAUCUAAUGAACAAAAAACUGCUACAGUGACGUCAUAAUUCUAUAAGGGCAAUAGUUGCCAAAUUUCCUCUGGUAUUAUUAGCAUUCUGCCUUUGCAUAGAUUAGCCUUCAAAUUUAUUAUUUUUAGUAUUAUUUGAUACGAUUGAAGUGGCUAAGAUUGAUUGAGCUUUUCUUGAUCACAUUUUCUGCUUCUUAGCUAAAGUAAUUUUAUUUAAAUUGACAUGGCUUGAGUUGUCAUCAUUUUCUGCUCUUCUAGAAUGAUGUGUAGAGAAAACUUGAAGAUACUAUCCCUUCUUUGGCAUUCUUCUCUUAAUGCUAUGCUAUUAUUUAUCAUAAUAUGCAUAUAUUUAGUUGUAUCUGGUAUCAUUCUAACACUCAUAACUACCAUUUUAGUUAAGUCCAACUUUAUAUUUGUUACAAUGCAGUGUUUUGGGAAAGGUCUAUUAGUAAUUAUUUAAGUAUUACAUAUUUUUAUGGAAGUCUUUAGAAGGUGAAGAUCUUACUGAGAAACUAUUUUCUAAAUAAAUUUAAUUUUCUUUUGUAUUUGUAUCAGAUCAUGCCUACUGUAUGUUAGAUUUUAGACUAUUUUAAAAGAAACCGUAGAUUAUAUAAAAAUUUUUUUGCUGUUUUUAAAUGGCAUUUGUCUUAUGUUUAAUUUCACAGGAUGAUUUUGAUAGACAAAUUUUAGAAAACCUUUUUUCAAAGGUAAUGGUUCUAUCAGUUUCAUUCCAACAGUAGCUAAUUUCUGUGUUUCAGUCCUACAGAAAUUGUGUGAGUAGUUGAAAUAAUGUACAUGUACUAGUUUUUUUAAGUAUUCUAAAUAGUUCUAACAUUUAAUGCAUAUCAGAAACAUGCUUAAGAAAUAACAAUAUCCAGGCCCACCCCACCUAUUGAAUCAGACAGUUCCCAGGGCAUAUAUAUGCUGGGGAAGCCCCAUAGGUGAUUUUAAUGUAUACCAAACAUGUAGAGUCUCACUCUGUUGCCCAGGCUGGAGUGCAAUGACGUGAUCUCAGCUAACUGCAACCUCUGCCUCCUGGAUUCAAGCAAUUCUCCGGCCUCAGCCUCCUGAGUAGCUGGUACUACAGGUGCGCGCCACCACACCUGACUAAUUUUUGUUAGAGAUGGGGUUUCAUUCUGUUGGCCAGGCUGGUCUCGAACUCCUGACCUCAGGU